CUCGUUGGCCCUGCGGCGCUGGAGCCUUGACGCACGGAGCUCGAGAGCGAGAACGGGAGAGAAAGGGGUAGAAAUGGCGGCUCCGCUCGGCUCCCGCUGAGGAGGGCGAAGCCGGCGGAGUGUCUGUGCUGCCGGUCUGCAGCACCGCCCCCGCUUCCCGCACGCCGCCUGCUCACGCCGACUUCCCUUCCUCUGCCCGGCUCUCUCUUGUGCUCGUCUGCGCUCCGCACGCUCCGGGCCGGCUCGUCUCUCAUUGCCCGGCUCGGCUCCGCUGGCCCUGACUGACCGGCCGGCGGGCCGGCCUUGCUCGGCUCUCCCGGGCGCGGCGUGGACUCCGUCCCCCUGGCUGGACCAUGGUGAACACCCGGAAGAGCUCUCUCCGCCUUCUCGGGUCCAAGUCUCCUGGUCCCGGGCCUGGGCCUGGGGCCGGAGCAGAGCCUGGGGCGACCGGAGGCAGCAGCCAUUUCAUCUCCUCUCGGACCCGCUCCUCCAAGACCCGCGCCGCCAGCUGCCCCGCCGCCAAAGCCGGGGGAAGCGGUGGCGCCGGCGUCACUCUGGAUGAGGCCAGGAAAGUUGAAGUUGAUGGUAGUUUAAGUGAUAGCCACGUAUCUCCUCCAGCCAAACGCACUUUGAAACAACCUGAUUCUGUUUGCAAAGACAAAUCAAAAUCACGAAGUACUGGUCAGCGAGAGGAAUGGAACUUAUCAACUGGACAGGCCAGGUUAACUUCUCAGCCUGGUGCUACAUUACCAAAUGGACAUAGUGGCUUAUCCCUUCGAAGCCAUCCCCUUCGAGGGGAAAAGAAGGGAGAUGGGGACCUUUCUUGUAUAAAUGGUGACAUGGAAGUCAGAAAAAGUUGUCGUUCCAGGAAAAACAGAUUUGAAAGUGUGAACCAGAGUUUGUUAUUUGAUCAACUAGUAAAUAGCACUGCUGAAGCUGUACUACAGGAAAUGGACAACAUUAACAUCCGACGGAAUCGUCGAUCAGGAGAAGUAGAACGACUUCGAAUGUGGACAGAUACAGAAUUUGAAAACAUGGAUAUGUAUUCAAGAGUGAAAAGGCGAAGAAAGUCACUAAGAAGAAAUAGUUAUGGGAUACAAAAUCAUCAUGAAGUUUCUACUGAGGGUGAAGAAGAAGAAUCUCAAGAGGAGGAUGGAGAUAUAGAAGUUGAAGAGGCAGAAGGAGAAGAAAAUGAUAGACCAUAUAAUUUGAGACAGAGAAAAACAGUGGAUCGAUACCAAGCACCUCCAAUAGUACCAGCUCAUCAAAAAAAGAGGGAAAACACGCUGUUUGAUAUUCAUAGAUCUCCAGCAAGAAGAAGCCAUAUUAGGAGAAAGAAGCAUGCCAUUCAUAGUAGUGACACAACUUCUUCUGAUGAGGAACGCUUUGAAAGAAGGAAAUCAAAGAGCAUGGCAAGAGCAAGAAAUAGAUGUUUGCCUAUGAACUUCAGAGCAGAGGACUUAGCUAGCGGUAUUCUCCGAGAACGAGUGAAAGUGGGUGCAAGCUUGGCUGAUGUUGAUCCAAUGAACAUUGAUAAAUCAGUACGGUUUGAUAGCAUAGGUGGAUUGAGCCAUCAUAUUCAUGCGCUAAAGGAAAUGGUAGUAUUCCCACUUUUAUAUCCAGAAAUUUUUGAAAAGUUUAAAAUUCAGCCUCCAAGGGGCUGUUUGUUUUAUGGCCCUCCUGGCACAGGUAAAACCUUGGUUGCCAGAGCAUUAGCUAAUGAAUGCAGCCAAGGAGACAAAAAAGUGGCUUUUUUUAUGCGAAAAGGAGCAGAUUGUUUGAGCAAGUGGGUUGGUGAAUCUGAAAGGCAACUUAGGCUUCUUUUUGAUCAGGCAUAUUUGAUGAGACCUUCUAUAAUAUUUUUUGAUGAAAUAGAUGGAUUAGCUCCAGUUCGCUCUAGCAGACAAGAUCAGAUCCACAGCUCUAUAGUAUCAACCCUCCUUGCUCUUAUGGAUGGAUUAGAUAAUAGGGGUGAAAUUGUUGUUAUUGGUGCUACAAACAGACUUGACUCUAUAGAUCCUGCACUCAGGAGACCUGGUCGUUUUGACAGAGAAUUCCUCUUCAACCUGCCUGAUCAAAAGGCAAGAAAACACAUCUUACAGAUCCAUACCAGGGACUGGAAUCCAAAAUUGUCAGAUGCAUUUUUAGGUGAAUUGGCUGAAAAAUGUGUUGGCUACUGUGGAGCCGAUAUCAAGGCCCUGUGCACUGAAGCCGCCCUGAUUGCACUGCGGAGGCGUUAUCCCCAGAUCUAUGCUAGCAGUCAUAAACUGCAGCUGGAUGUUUCCUCAAUAGUGCUUAGUGCCCAAGAUUUUUACCAUGCAAUGCAGAAUAUCGUGCCUGCUUCCCAACGUGCUGUGAUGUCUUCAGGGCAUGCACUAUCCCCCAUCAUAAGACCACUGCUGGAAAGAAGCUUCAACAACAUCCUAGCAGUCUUGCAAAAAGUGUUUCCUCAUGCUGAAAUUAGCCAGAGUGACAAAAAAGAAGAUAUAGAAACUUUAAUUUUAGAGGAUAGUGAAGAUGAAAAUGCUUUAUCAAUUUUUGAGACCAAUUGUCACUCAGGAUCACCAAAGAAACAGUCAUCAUCUGCUGCUAUACAUAAACCCUACCUUCAUUUUACAAUGUCACCAUAUCAUCAGCCAACCUCUUACAGGCCACGCUUAUUGCUCUCUGGAGAACGGGGCUCAGGUCAAACUUCUCACCUUGCUCCAGCACUUUUGCACACUCUAGAAAGAUUCUCUGUGCAUAGACUAGAUCUCCCAGCACUUUAUUCAGUUAGUGCCAAAACACCUGAGGAAUCAUGUGCACAGAUUUUUCGUGAAGCUCGAAGAACAGUACCUAGUAUUGUUUACAUGCCUCACAUUGGGGAUUGGUGGGAAGCUGUCAGUGAAACUGUGAGAGCAACUUUUCUGACAUUGCUACAAGAUAUACCAUCAUUUUCACCUAUAUUUUUAUUGUCUACCUCUGAAACCAUGUACAGUGAACUGCCUGAAGAGGUUAAAUGUAUCUUUAGAAUACAGUAUGAAGAGGUCUUGUAUAUUCAAAGGCCUAUUGAAGAAGACAGAAGAAAAUUUUUUCAAGAAUUGAUUCUCAAUCAGGCAUCAAUGGCUCCACCACGAAGGAAACAUGCUGCUCUUUGUGCUAUGGAAGUGCUUCCUCUUGCACUACCUUCUCCACCUCGUCAAUUAUCAGAAUCAGAAAAAAGUCGAAUGGAGGACCAGGAGGAAAAUACUUUAAGAGAGUUGCGGUUGUUUCUCAGGGAUGUAACCAAGAGGCUGGCCACAGAUAAACGCUUUAACAUCUUCAGCAAACCGGUUUCAGAUUAUCUUGAAGUAAUCAAGGAACCAAUGGACUUAUCAACAGUAAUAACUAAAAUUGAUAAACAUAAUUACCUGACUGCAAAGGAUUUCCUGAAAGAUAUUGACCUCAUCUGUAGCAAUGCUUUAGAGUAUAAUCCAGAUAAGGACCCAGGAGAUAAAAUAAUUAGGCACAGGGCUUGUACCCUGAAGGACACUGCACAUGCUAUCAUUGCAGCUGAAUUAGAUCCAGAAUUUAAUAAACUUUGUGAGGAAAUUAAGGAAGCAAGAAUAAAAAGAGGCUUAUCAGUAACAUCAGAACAAAUAAAUCCUCAUAGUACUGGAGCUCGGAAGACAGAAACUAGAGUCGAAGAGGCAUUUCGGCACAAACAAAGAAAUCCAAUGGAUGUGUGGCACAACUCUGCAAAUAAAUGUGCAUUUCGGGUUCGGAGAAAAUCAAGGCGGAGAUCACAGUGGGGUAAAGGAAUUAUUAAGAAAAGGAAAGUUAAUAAUUUAAAAAAAGAUGAAGAAGACACCAAAUUUGCAGACUAUGAGAACCAUACGGAGGACAGGAAAUUAUUAGAGAAUGGAGAGUUUGAGGUAAGCACUGACUGCCAUGAGGAAAAUGGAGAAGAGACUGGAGACUUAUCUAUGACCAAUGAUGAAUCAUCCUGUGACAUCAUGGACUUGGACCAGGGGCAGAGGCUUAACAAUGGAGCAGGCACAAAAGAGAACUUUGCAUCUACUGAGGAGGAAAGUUCAAAUGAAUCUCUACUGGUCAACAGCAGCAGUUCCUUAAACCCGGAGCAGACCUCCAGGAAAGAGACUUUCCUUAAAGGAAAUUGUCUAAAUGGUGAGGCUUCCACUGACAGUUUUGAAGGAAUACCAGUUCUGGAAUGUCAGAAUGGCAAGCUUGAAGUAGUUUCUUUCUGUGAUAGUGGAGAUAAAUGUAGUUCUGAACAAAAGAUUCUUCUGGAGGACCAGUCAAAAGAAAAACCAGAAACUUCGACUGAAAAUCAUGGAGAUGAUCUUGAGAAACUAGAGGCACUGGAAUGUAGCAAUAAUGAGAAGUUAGAACCUGGCUCUGAUGUGGAGGUUAAAGAUGCAGAACUGGAUAAAGAAGGUGCUUCUAAAGUAAAGAAAUACCGUAAAUUAAUUUUAGAGCAGGCAAAAACGACAAGCCUGGAACUGGUUCCAGAAGAGCCAUCUGAGCCUGUGCCUCCUCUUAUAGUUGAUCGUGAGAGAUUGAAGAAAUUGCUUGAUUUGUUGGUGGAUAAAAGCAACAAUCUGGCAGUUGAUCAGCUUGAGAGAUUAUAUUCUCUUCUUAGUCAGUGUAUCUACCGUCAUCGUAAAGAUUAUGACAAAUCACAACUUGUAGAGAUGAAGCACAGCUUCAGGGAAAGAAAUUCUGUGCCAGCUAGUCCUUUUCUUCUCCUCCCUGAUGAGCUUCAAGCCAUGGAAGGUAAAAGAAGGCGAGAGUGGAGGAAAAAGACGUGCCUACUUCCCCUGCAUCUUUGCCAUGUUUGUAAGUUUCCUGAGGCCUCCGCAGCCAUGCUUCCUGUACAGCCUGCAGAACUGAGGCACGUAGAGUCUGGUUAUCCUCCUUAUUGUGAUGUCAUCAGUGACUGAUAUUUGAUGCCUAAAUACAUUAGAGCCUGCAGAAUGGCAUGAAAAGGAAGCCCUUCGUGACAUUGCUUUGAAACUGAGGACAAGACGAGAUAGACGGACAGAAUGGUGAGAGCCGGGAGGAGGGGAGAGGAAACAACCAAGGACUUCCGCCACAGACAGCCAGCAGCCAUGACCUGGGGCCUGGCCCGGGGCGGGCCCUCCUGCCACAUGGAACACGGGGUCAGAGGUCAGAGUGGCCUGCGUGUAGAGUGUGCGUCGGGCUGGGGAACUGGGGGGAGCAGGGGAGGGACACAAAUAUAUAAAUCUGUUUAUAUCUGGUGUCUACAGGAAUACAAAACCAUUGCAAAGGCUCCUAAGGCCUGGCAGCUGCCCCUAAAGCUGGACCUGGAAGGAAACAGAUAAGAUGAAGCAAGAGUGACACUGAUACAUAAGUGACAGCAGGAGUAAAAACACCUGCCGCGUUAGGAGUCCGGAGGCGGCCCCGCAGGCCGUCGGCUUGGCCGCCCCAUCCUGGCUCCUCUGAGUAGCCCUGCUUCCCACCCUGAGCCCGGUCCUGCCUCGGGCUGGGCCUGGCCACGUGGCUGGGAAAUGACCUCUGUGGUCCACUCACUCGCUUCUCAGGAGGCCACAGGGCAAGAUGCUUGUGACGGGUCCCUUGCGCGCACCUGCGGCUGGCGGUGGGGCUGUCGAGGUGUCCAGCAAGCGAGCAGGCUGGCCGCAGAGAGGCCAGCUGCUGGGUGUGUGGGUGGGCGGAAAGAGCAGGGGGCAGGGAGCUGGGGGCACUGGGUGCCUGGGCUCUGCCACCCACAGGUGGGCAGCCUUGGUCUCCCGGGCCCUCAGCCUCCUCUUCUGCAAAAUAAGAGGAUGGAACUAGAUGAGGUCUGAAUUCCCUUGGAGAUUUUGUGACAGAGGCUGGAAAAUGCCCUUCCCACGAGACUCUUCCCUACGUGGCAGUACCUGAAAUUCCACCAUUAGAGCGACAUUCUCUGAGGUCAGGCACCGCCCUCCCAGGGCCUCAGCACAGGCAUGGCCAGGAGGAGAGGGGGAGGUGCAAUCCUGCUGCGGAGCUGGCGUCCAGCCUCUCUCCCAGCGUGGCCACAGUAGGCCCUCCCCACACAACGGCUCAUCCCACCAGGACCCCAAGGGGCCUCUGCCUCCAAGCCCGGGGCCAGCCCAGAAGGCAGAGGGGGCAAGGUGUGGACUCCACAGAGGCCCCUCCAAACCCCCCAACACAGAGUGACUUCUAAAGUGAAUUCACACACCUAGUCUUCUGCUGUCAGGAUGGAUUUCCAUACCUCGGUGGCUUUGUUAAGCGUAAAAAUAAUUCACUACGUGAUCACUUAAAAUCACAGAAAUCCUCAACACCCCCGGCCCCAGAGCCAUCUGGUCAACCUCGUACUCCUGUCUUUGCUGCCUGGGACUUCAUUCCUACAAGCCGCUGUCCAGCCUCUCCUCUGCAUGCCCUUUCUGCCCUGUGGAGGUCACACUGGGCCACAGCCUUCUCCCGAGGCCCCCAGUCACUGCUGCCUUCACCUCUGGCCAGCCCACUUGUCCACCCAGGAGUCCUCAGGCAGAGGAGCUCAAAGCCAGUGAAGGGCUGAGCCCAGGGGGACUUCAGGAUGUGCGAGCACAUGCACACGCACACAUAUGCACUGACCCUAAGAGCCGUGAAGUCCCCCGGUGGGGAGGGGUGCUGGGCAGACGGACAGUCCAUGGCUGAGUGACAGGUGCGAUGGGACUCACAUGGCUGCCCUGAGGGGUGCUGCCUGUCUUGCCCACAGUCUGAGCCAGGGAGUGGGUCCUGGCCACCAGGCACAGGAGGAGGGACACAGGUGCCGUGGAGCAUCGCAGGUGCUGUCUAGACUGAGGAGGACCCCUGGCCACAGGAGGCAUGGCUGUGGCUCUGUUCCUCCUGGCCCCUUGUGAGGGUCACCUGUGGGGUGGAGGGGGCCGCUGGGCAGAUGAUCUGCAGGGAAAGGCCGCAGAGGCACAGGGGAAUGUGAUGGGGGCUCUUUCAGAAUCUGAGUUCAAAGAGGAGGCGAGGCCCCAGAGGGCGAGGGCUGUGCCUCUUACCAACACACACGGUUCUCAUCCACACAGGCCUUCGUGCAUGGCCUGCAGAGCUGUGAGGGGGUGGGGGCGCCUCUGUAUCCCUGGACAUCAGACUGUCUUGGGACUGGACCCCAGUGCUCCUUAGGCCUCUUCUCUCUGAACAGGGACCCCAGAGGGGACACCCCCGUGAUGGGUGACCCUGGUCGCUGACGAGGGCUGCGUCCUCCACAGGUGGCUGUUCUGUCCCUGCCCCAAGCCAUUUCUUGUCCUGUCCUACCGGGCCCCAUGGAGUGAAUGGCUUGGGGUGCUGCUGGCCCAUCAGGUCAUGAUGUGGCUUUGGAGGGACUGCAGCAGGGCAGACGGGCAGCACUAACCCUCUCUAUGAAGCUGACGCAGGGGGGUGGGGUAUAGAGUGAGGGCAGGCUGGUGCUCCCCAGCCACACAGGCCCCAUGGGGUCUGUCAGAAGACCAGAGCUUCCUGGAGUCACCUACUUCUGGGCGUGGGGGUGCCCAGGAGAGGCCAGAGUCCGGGACGCAGCCUCUGCUCAGCAGAGGAAUGGCUAGGCCCAACUACUAGAAUGUUUGCAAUCCCACCAUUAGCCACAGACUCAUCCAGGAUUAGAAAUGCCCUUCCUUCCAGACAUCAGGAUGGAGGCCCUCAUCCACCCUCAUGCACCUCAGAGAUCAGAUGUUUUCAUUUUGCAAGUUGGAACUGGGCACUGUCUGGAGCAAUGAGAGGAAUCCAUGGGCAGUGGUGGGUGAGGGACAGGCAUGGGGCAGGUGGCUGGUACCCAGCUCUGCUCAGAAGAGAGGACUCCGCCCAUGAAUGAACGCCUGGGCGUGUCAUCAGCUGCAGGACACACGCAUGGGCAUGCACCCAGUCUCCCUGGGUCUUGGGGAUUUGUGUGGCUCAGGCCCACCCUUGGUAACUUGGUGACAGGUGUGGGUGACGCCAUUGUGCCAGCAUCCAAGAUGAGACAUGGGAGUCUCGUUAUCUGGCUUCCAAGCCACACCUGUCCACUCUACCGAGGUGCUGCCACCCACACAUGCUCAGGGAAGAGGGUGAAGGGUGUGGGGCUCUGGGCAGGACUUUGCCGGGACCCUUCUGCAUGGCCAUGGGGGGCAGCCAAGCCCAAAGGGACUCGGCCGCAGGCUGGGAGAGGACACUGAGACCCAGCUCUCCCGCUCAUGGUCUGACUGUCAUCUUUACAAAACACACAUCUGGUCGCAACGCCCCCAGGCUCCUGUGACCCAGGUCUAGCCUCCCUCCAGCCGCGUCCCCUGCAAGCCACCCUCAUACCCGGCCCUGCAGCAACGUGGAGUCACCUGUGGGACCUGAGACCCCCUCCCGCCUUUCGACCUUGCUCUUCCCCACUUGUCUGCCCGGACAAUGCCCAUUCUUCAUAACCCACAUCAGAUGCCACCUCUCCAAGGAGCCUCUCUGAAUGACCCUCCCCCACAGCCAGGCCCUUGGACCACAAGUCUCUGAAGCAUCGUCUCUGCUCGUCUCCUUGCCUGUCUGCAGCGUGUCCCCACCAGACUGUGGGCUCAGCUGGUGUUUGGUGUGAGCCCCGGCCCCAGGAGGGGCUCCUGUGUGUUUGCUGAGUGACGAGCCAGUGAGUGACUUGAAUUCCCAUUCUGUCCUGUGGCUGUGGGGCAGGGCGUCUGCACUGGGGUUGGGUCUGGCAGGCACCGUCCUUGCCAGGCUUGGGUGCUGGGUCAUUGUCCUCCCUGGGGCUGGAGUGGUGGACACAUCACCUGUCCCAGGCUGGUGGUGGGAGUCUAGUCUGAGCCUCCAGACCUGGGGAUGCGGGGACAGCAGGGAGGGAUCACCUGCCCCUGGCAGGGCUCACCCAGGGAGGGCCAAUGUUGAUCCCCACGGAGGUCUACACCAGGACAGAGGUCCCAGAGAAGGUCCCUACUCCCUCCCCUUACAAGAGUGCAGCUGCCUGAGCGUGGAGCCACUGCUUGGGGUCAAAGGGCAGGGCCAUGGCUCUGCACUGGGCCAAUCCGGCCACUGCACAGUAAGUCUCCAGGGUCACGGAUGCCAAGGGGACUGAAAAGACAUGGUUACAUCAGCUUCUCUCUUGACCACCAAGAAUGUGAAAUUCUCUAUGAUUUUACACGGCAGGAAAGGAAGCCAUCUUCUUGUAAAGACUUGGCUUUCCUCCCAAGAAGGCACUUCUUGGUCAUGUGUGCUCUGUGGCUGCAAACGAACACGGCGACUUUCAGCCACAGGGCACCCUGGGCUUGGCUUUGGCUUCCCCUCCUUUUUCCUGUGUGACCUUACUGUAUGCUGAAGGCCCCCCAGCCCCAUCUCUACAAACCUCAGACCUCUCUGGGUUCAGUUCCAUGCACCUGGCUGCCUACAGGUGGCCCAACCUGGGGACCUGGGCGUCCGUCAGGCUGCUCAGCUUGACACACCAGAUGGUCAACUGCUCAUCUCCCCAGCUCUCCCGACACUGGCCUGUGGACCUGCUCUCCUCCCUGUGACCUCUGAUGCCCGUGACCUCUGAUGCCCGUGACACCUCACCUCCUUGGGUCCUGGUGCUUGCCUUUCCGUCCUGGUCCUGCCCAUCCUCUGCCCAUCCCCCGGAGGUGUCAGAGCUGCAAGGAGACCUGGGCAUCACUUGAACCAAUUUCCUGAUUUAUAGAUGAGAAAGCCCAGGGCGCAGGAGAGGACGUGACCAGUCUGAGGUCACAAGACAAGCGGCGGAGUCAGGCGUAGGACCCAGGUCUCCUACCUGCCAAGGUGGGGAUGUCCUCUCUCCUCCAGCCCCAUCCUUUCUGAUGAGGGCCACCGAGACACAUCCUACUGUUCUCCUUCCUUCAGGUGGGCGUCCCCUCCCCACUGCUCUUGAAGUUACCCACCUCAGACCAUGCCCAGGUCCUAGCAUGGGGUCAGGGCUUGCCUGCCCCAGUGCAGCCCCCUCUGGAGGGCCAUCUGCCCCACCCUGCCCUUCCCCACUCAUGCCCCAUCCCCGGCCUGGAAUGCUCUUCCUCCCUCUUCUCAGCCCAAGAAGCCUUCACUACUUUGGGUUCCCUCCUAGCACGUGUUCUUCUCUGUUGUGUGCAAGUCUGGCUUUCAAUGUGCGGUCUCUGAAAGCCAUCCGAGGGCCCUGUGCUCCUCUCACCCACCACGUUCUAGCUGGGGACUAGGCUGCCGCUCAGCACUGACCUGCCCCCUUUCUGUCCUCUCUAGCUGGUUUGGAGCCAGGCCCAAGACCCUAGGACGCUCAUCCAUGAUCCGGCAGCCCGAUGCGGGCCCCUGCUGUCCAGGAUUUGUCAAGAGUGGCAGCACAGAGUCCUCCCUGGCCUGGUGAGGCCACUAGACAUGUCCCUUCACCCCAGACCACAUGCCCCUAACCCCUGUGCUUGGACAGAGAGAGCCCAAGCACCGGGGGCAGGAGACCUGAGGUGUCCAUGAGAUGGGAAGUCCCAAAGAGCCUGCCCCUUCCUGCGAGGCUGAGGGCCGGCAUGUGGCCAGCCAGAGCCUGCCCACAGGGCAGCUGGGCUCUAUGUGAAAGGCCGGAUCGGAGAGGAGAUGCCAGCCAGGGAUCCAUCCUGAAACAAAACACAGUCACUCCGGGGUUAGUUGGCAAGUCCAAACACGGCAUUGGGAAGCAGAGGUCCUGUCCUCCCUCUGAGCACAGUCCCGGCUCAGCGUCUGCCCCGGAGAGGCUGCAAGGCAAGAGGAGCAGCGGCGUUAAUCUGCUGAGGGCUGAGAGAAACGUGAGCGUUACCCUGGGCUGGCCCCUUGGCUGCUCUCCCUUACUACGGAGCUGGAAGGUGGCCCCUGACUUCUUUGCAAAGGUAUGAAGCAGACAAAUUAAAAAAUCAACAUAAUGGAGGAAAAAAAAAAAGAUGCUCAUGCACCAAUAAGACUCAUUCAGGUAGAAAUAGCCAGGGCAGAGGGCAGGAGGGAGGGAGCAAGGGUUGAGAGAGACCGUGUUUAGGACACACCUGGUCUAUGCUCCACAGCGCCGGUUUAGGCUCACUGCACAAGGAUCAGACAUGCAGUGUGGCCCAGGCAUUGCUACAAGUCUCUUCUCCCCUACUUGGGCUGGGGAAAAGCAGCCCCGGGGGCACCUUGUGCUCCUCAGCAGGGACAGCCUGGCCGAUGCGCUUUCCUGGCAUUAGUCACCACCGACAGCAGGGACGAUGGCACUGGGGAUCCUGCUCUGGCCCGGUGGGGGCAGUGUGUAGUGAUCCCUUAAAAUGGAGCCUACAGUCCCCCCUAAUCUCAGGGACAGCUUGUGAGCCACUGAGAACCUGGGAUCUCAGGGGUGGGGCACGGUGUUGUCUACUGCUGGCAGAGGCCCCUGGUGACCAGCAAAGCUGGUGACAGCAAAGCUGUGGGUGGGGGCGGGUGCUGGGCGCAGUGGCUGCUCUGAGGCUGUGUGUGAGAGGGUACUGGGGAGGAGGAGGAGGAGGAGGAGGAGAGAUGGCUACUGGCUCUGUGACAGGGAGUCACGCUUCAGGAACCUGCAAGAGAGGGGAAGAGAAAAGCGACACAAAAGCGUCCUACAAAGGAACAGACCCGACCACAGCUGGAAGGAAGGCAAACCUUUGAAUCAGGUCCUUGAAAUACAAGCUGCAGGAAGCUAGAACAUUUUGGUGGACUUCAAACUCUCUGCCUUCAACAACAAUUUUCAGGUCUGUAAACGCUUUCGCUCUGCGUUGCUGGUUCAAUUCCUUCAACAUUUCUGCAGAACAGAGAAGACAGACAGGGCCAGGUUCCCAUUAAGAGUUUUUUUUUUUUUAAUUAAAAAAAGUUUUUUUUCUUUUUUCAAGAAGUAGAGAAAUAGGAAAUACUUGAUAUUGUUUCUUGGCAAGACUGGCUCAACACUGACAGUCAAAAGAAGUCACAAACAUAAUGCAUAAACAAGCAGCCACUGGGAGGGGCUAAUAACCAAAGGAAUCACAACUUUAAAAAGCAAAAAAACCAAAUAUGAUACAAAAAAUCAAACCCAGAAAUUGAAAGGUUGGGGGAGAGAUUCCCAUACUGACGAUUGGAAACAUAGAGAAUACAUUAUCACAGACAACUAAAAACUGUCAAAUAACUACGGAGCAAGUUCUCCAAAUGCCAAUGGGUGCCGAUGUAUUGGAGACCAAGUCAAGCAUGGCACUGUGAUGUAAGAUGGGCUGGAUAUGGUUCAAAGGAAUCACAACCACAAAACCUGCAAAAACAGCGUCCCUUAUGUUAGACACUCACAGCCAUGGCGUGGGAGGAGACCCCGAGAAAGGAGGGGGCCAUGGGAGGCCUGGCAAGCACCUCCUUCUGUUUCACACUUGUGGGGACUUUUCGGGAAAGCAAGCAAGCAAGGGACAGGGACCCUCUGCGCCUCCUCCCAUGUCCCAGUUGAGUCUCUCAGGACACCCACCCUCUCCUGGGGCUUUGACAUGGGGCAGAGCCUGCUUUACAGCCCGGCAGAUCCCAGGAAGUGGCCUCGGAGGCUCCCACUCUGCUGCACACCUACCUGUGCCCGGUGUCUUGGACCUGGGGCUGGCACAGACAGUGCCCGGGCCCAUGGGCUCCAGACCUGGGGAUGUCAGAAGCUUCUCCCAGACCCACCCCAAGGCUUAGAAAGGAGAAGGAGGGAAGAGCCUGCCAGUCACCCUGUUGGGGUUGCACACUCUCUUUCAUUGGCAAAAGUUAGGGCCUUCAGUUGACCACUGCUCCCCACAACAGCCUUGCCUCAUCUGCCUGCCCCCAGGAUCCCCUGGGCAAAGCCUGCCCUUAAUGUUGCUGGCAGCUGCGCGUCAGAGGCCCUGAUCCUUGGGCCAGAAUGACCUAGACUGUCUUCAGGCCAGGCGAUUUCCCUUGGCAGGUGUGUGGGAGAGGGUGGCCUGCAGAGCUGAGCCCUGCUCUCCAGCCCCACCGGCCAUCGCCCCUGCUCCAGCCUCAUUGGUUGUUGCUGUCCACAUGGGCCAGGGCCGGCUGCCCGCCAGGACUCCUUCCUGGCCCCAGCCCUGCUUCUGACACUUGGCCAAGACCCUUUGUCUCUCUGAGCCUCUGCUUCUGCAUCUGUAAAAUGGGGAUUGAGGAUCCUGCUUCUGCUCCCUGAUUGCCAGGCAGGCCCUUUUUGGUGAGGACACACUGGGCUCUGCUGAAGACCAAGGAAGACGGUGGGAGGGGCUCCUGGAGAACACGCCACAUGCAUGUUCAGGGAUCGGGGUUGGGGGCCCUGCCCUCUGGGAGCCAUGGCAAGGCCGAAUCACUGACCCCGCCAACCCCAAGUCACACUGAGUCUGGAGUCACAGCAGAGCAUCUCCAGGGGUGCGGAAGGGGGCUCUGGCUGGGACUUCAGGAAGGAUCUACGUGGGGUGAGCUCAGACCCGGAGCAAGGGGGGUGGGAGCUACAGACAGAGACCAACAGGCUCAGAGCACCAGUGGGAGGGCGCGGGAGGGUGCGGGAGGGUGUGGGAGGGUGCAGGAGCACGAGGGGGCAGGUGCAGGUGGACAAAAGGGCCAUGGGCAACAGGGAACACAAUGAGGCGGUGGGCGGGGCCAGAUCGCAACAGUCUUGCCUGGGAGCUCCAGCUUCAUCCUGGGGCACCAGGGAGCCACAGGGGAUUCUGGACAGGAAGUGGCAAGGUUAGACUUGGGUUUCAGACAAAUCCACACAGAGGCAGGAUGGGGAGUGGCUUGGGAGGCCAAUGGGAGGCAAGAUAGCGCCGUGCAGAGAGUUGAGCCUCGAAGCCAGACCUGAGGGUGAACCUGCACUGGGCCUCCUAUCAGCUCUGUGACCUUGGGAAAGGGGACCCACAUCCUCAGAGCCUCAGGGUCCACACUUGUUGAAGGUUCCAUGAGACAGCAUGUGGCGGGCACACAGGGAGCGCUCAGCGGGUGGGAGUGUGCAGUGCUGCUGAUGGUGACGGUCUUUCCGAGGGAGAGGUGAGAAGGCCGGAAUUACACAGCAACAGCAGGACAGAGAAACAGGAGCGUGUGGACCCCGUGGGGCUCAGUGCAGGAAGGAAGUGGGGAGGGGGAGGCAUGGAGACCACUAACAGGUUUUUGGAGGGGAUGGUGGUGGGACAUCAGGAAGGGAGGGAACAAGAAGAUCAGUUGUGGGGUGGGGCCUGUGGGACACCUGGGGGAUGGGGUAGGAGGCGGUGGAUAGAGGCCUGGGCUAGAGACAAGGUAGAGAGCCCAGCGGCGCCUGCGCACAGCCCAGGCGGAGGGGAGACAGCACAGGGCCAGUUGCAGGGCCAGGCUGGAUAAGGCUCAGCUGCCAUGCUCACACGUAUCUCCAGAAAGAGUCACCAGCCGAAUUAAUGCCCAAACCACGAGCCAGGUAGAUGACAUCCCCUUUUUGAGUGAAGCGGUAGGGGAGGGGACAGAAUUCUGGGCUGGGAUUCUGAAGACCUGGAUCCUGGUUCUUGUUCCAGCACUGCCACUAAUUGGUGUGUGACCCUGGGCCAGCACCCCAGCUUUCUGGGCCUCUGUUUCCUCUAGCACAGAAGGGCAGAGACACCUGCUUGGUAGCCCCCUGGGUGUCAUGCUGCAGAGAGUGACAGAUGUGGCCCCACAUGCCUGCUGAGUUAAUCAGUGCUUAGGGGCCUGGAAAACACAACAGCACACAAAUGCCUACUCUUUCUGGGCCCGAGGCAUCCUGAGGGUUUCUGAAGACCUUCCUUUCAAAUCGAGGUCCCGGCAAUGAUUCUAUCUAAAGCCCCAGCCCCGGCCGUGACACCUUCUGCUCCAGGAAUUCUGGAGCUAGACCUGGAAGGCGCUUGGAGGUUCAGGUGUCCCCAUCCUAAUGUAGGUGCUUUCUGCUCUCUCUGAAUCUCACUUGGUGGAAAUCUGGAUUUAAUAGUUGGGGAAGAUUAUUCACUUUCAGAAGAAUUUUUCAAUUUAUGAAAGUGCUCACCAGGGGAUUCCCAGCAGGCCCCAAGUGCAUUCCUAGUAUCGAUUGGCUGGUGUGUGCGGGCUGCUGCCCACUGCCUGCCCGGCCGGCGAAGCAGGAGCUUAGGCUCUCAGGCUGUGCCUGUCGGUGGGGAGACCCAGAAUCCACAAGGGGACACCAGGACCCGCUGGGCACAGGCUGCCCUCCUCCCUGCCCCAUGUUUUGGCAAAGGACACUCCCUGAUCUCUGAGAAGCUUCCAAGUGAGGUGUGUGGGAUUGCUGCGGGGUCUGGGGAGAUCUUCCAACAACAUGGCCUAUUCUCAGGUGUGGGAGAUUUGCAGGCCUCGGGGCUGGGUCUUCAGAGUGGACUUCCAGAAGCACCUGGCACCCUGCACUAUCCUGCUCCAGGAUUCUGCGGGAGAAGAUGAUGGCCUAGAGACCCCAGGAGAAGAUGGCCUAGAGACCCCAGGAGAAGAUGGCCUAGAGACCCCAGGAGAAGAUGGCCUAGAGACCCCAGGGGAAGAUGGCCUAGAGACCCCAGGGGAAGAUGGCCUAGAGACCCCAGGGGAAGAUGGCCUAGAGAGCCCAGGAGAAGAUGGCCUAGAGACCCCAGGAGAAGAUGGCCUAGAGAGCCCAUGACCCUCCCUGCAUGGAGGCUCGGUGGGGUCUGGCGAGUGGAGUCCUGGCAGCUGAGCCUACCAGGUGGGAUGAAGACUUGGCCUCAGCAUCUGUCCCUGUUGGUCGGCCCCAGAGGUUGUUUUUGGGUCUCCUCGGCUUUGAGCGGGAUGCCCGCCUACGUCUGUGGGACUGCACACCCUGGCCUUGCUCACGGAAGUGGCUUCCCCAUGCUCAGAUUUUUGUCCCAGGCCUCUUUGCCCCUUUCCCCACUUCCUCCUGCAUGCCCAGGAUGCUCGACUCAGCGCCCAGCAUGGAGCUCCUCUUCCCGUGGAAGACGGUCCACUGCCCGCAAUCCGCAGGCCUUCCCCAGACUCCUCCCCUCCCUCAUCACACCAAGUCCCAUCUUUUUACCUCCUAGAAUUCUCAGGAUCCAGCCUCUCCUGCCCUAGGCCCUCCAGCACCCUGAGUGAGCUGCCCUCAUCUUUCACUUGAGUCACUGCAACAGCCUCUGAGGAUGUCUCCCUGUUUCCAGCCUGUCCCCCUCCAGGCCACCUCCACACUGCAUCCUCACAGCCACUGGCCACACAAAUCCUUCGGGGCUGAAGGGGCAGCACAGCCCUCUGGGAGGUCUCCCCGUUCCCUCCGCUCCUCCUCCACUCCCAGGGGACCCUUUGCUCCCCAGCGAAGCCUCCUUGCACCCCACACACGUCCCCACUCCAAGUCUCCGUCCCCUCCGCCUGGAUCUUCCCUCCCCUUCCUCCAUCUGGCCAAGCAGUAUUUAUCCUUCACCACCAGGGAAAGUGUUAUUUUGUCCUGGGCCUCUUUGCCUCCUUCCCCUCUUCCUCCCACACCCUCUGCCCUCUGCCCUCCUCCGGAGGCUGGCAGAACAACUUGUGCUCACUUCUUUAUCGAUACUAGGAGUUGUAAUUAUUUAUUUACAUGUCUGCCUCCUGCACUAGACUAUGUUUUAUUCAUAUUUUUAUCUUCGACACUCAGCACAGGGCCUGGCAUACAUAUAUAUAUAUCUGGUGUGAUGGAUGGCAAAUAUUCUUUGUAGCUUCCCCCGUCAAGAGGUGGAGAUGAUUUCCCUACCCUUUGAAUCUUGGCUGGCUUUGUGAUUUGCUUUGGACUACAGAAUGUGGUGGAAGUGACCCUGUGAAAAUGUGAGUCACGGCCUUAAGAAGCUUUGCUCACUUUCACUCACUCUCCAGGGACCCCUGGCACCACCACCAUAGGAACAAGCCUGGGCUAGCCUGUUGGAGCAUGAGAGACUGUGUGGAGCAGAAACGAGCUGUCCCAGAUGAGGCAUUUAGACCAGCCAGUCUCUGCCAAUAUCAGCCAGGCCUGACCUAGAUUGGCUGAGUGUAGUCCAAACUGCUAAACCAGGAUCACAAUCUAAAUAAGUGGCUGUUUUUAAAACACUCAAUUUUAAGUCACUGAAUUUUAGAAUUGUUUGUUAAGCAGCAAGAGCUAACUGAUACACAAGGCAUGAAUAGAUGAUGGACUCAAGUGCUCAGGGAACUUUCCCUGUGUUGGUUUCACCUUUGCUAGUUCAGUUUGAGGCUAAUUCUUUUUUUUUUUUUUUAGUUGUGGUAAAAUGUACCCAUUUUAAAGUGUCCAGUUCAGUUGUGUUAAGUAUAUUCACACUGUUGGGCAAUCCUCUGGAAUCCUUUUCAUCUUCACAAACGGAAACUCCACACCCAUUAAACAACCACUCCCCACCUCCCCUCCACUCAUCCCCGGCAACCACCAUUCUACUUUCUGUCUCUAUGAGUUUGACUAUUUUAGACCCUCUUAUAAGUGGAAUUAUGCAAUAUUUGUCCUGUGAAUGGCUUUAUUUCACCUAGCAUAAUGUCCUUAAGGUUCACCCACAUGGUAGCAUGCAUCAGGAUUUCCCUCCUUUUUAAGGCUGGCUAAUAUUCCACUGUAUGUAGAUACCACAUACUGUUUAACCAUUCAUCCUUUGAUGGACGCUUGGGUUGCUGCCACCAUUUUGCUAUUGUAAACAAUGCUGCUAUGAGCACUUAUUUAGACUGUGACUCUGGUUUGGCAGUUUGGGCUACACUCAGCAGAUCUAGGUCAGGCCUGGCUGAUAUUGGCAGAGACUGGCCGGUCUAAAUGUCUCAUCUGGGACAACUCAUUUCUGCUCCACGUGGUCUCUCAUGCUCCAACAGGCUAGCCCAGGCUCAUUCCUAUGAUAGUGGUGCCAGGGGUCCCCGGAGAGUGAGUGAAAGUGAGCAAAGCUUCUUGAGGCCAUAGCUCCCAUUCAGUUCUCACCCCCGAGUUAUGGACCAGAUAUCCCCUCUAACGACCCGUCUCAAACCCCAUUGGUUCUAAGUGGUGAGUGUAAAAUGGCUCUGUGGAUGCAGCGGCAAGUGGCACGAGGGAAUGGGGACUGGAAGAGGCUCUGCCUGGGGCUGGAUGCUUUGCCUAGAGGAGAGUGAAGCCACAAACAGAACCAAGGCUGGAGAUGAAGUUGCAGCCAAACUUCUGCAUAUUUUUCACCAAACGACACAAGUUAUUUGUCAGAGACUAAUGGGCUCGUUCUGGCUGGCCUAUAAGGGCUGUAUGAGAUGGUAAUAAAGAGGAAGAGAUGUCAAAUAUUAAAAGGCAAAGAAUUUCAGUGGCUUUGCAGCAGAGAAGUCCAUUAAAUCAGAGCCUUGAGAAA